AGUGACAAGGUAAUUAAGACGAAGGAAACAAUUCUAGGAGGCACAACGUGGGGUGGACAGUCAGCUGUCGGUGGCUUCUGCUGAGAUGGCCACAGGACUCCAGGUUCCCCUGCCGCAGCUGGCCACAGGACUGCUGCUUCUCCUCAGUGUCCAGCCCUGGGCUGAGAGUGGGAAGGUGCUGGUGGUGCCCACUGAUGGCAGCCACUGGCUCAGCAUGCGGGAGGCCUUGCGGGACCUCCAUGCGAGAGGCCACCAGGUGGUGGUCCUCACCCUGGAGGUGAAUAUGUACAUCAAAGAAGAGAACUUUUUCACCCUGACAACGUAUGCCAUUUCAUGGACCCAGGACGAAUUUGAUCGCCUUUUGCUGGGUCACACUCAAUCGUUCUUUGAAACAGAACAUCUUCUGAUGAAAUUUUCUAGAAGAAUGGCAAUUAUGAACAAUAUGUCUUUGAUCAUACAUAGGUCUUGUGUGGAGCUACUGCAUAAUGAGGCCCUGAUCAGGCACCUGCAUGCUACUUCCUUUGAUGUGGUUCUAACAGACCCCUUUCACCUCUGCGCGGCGGUGCUGGCUAAGUACCUGUCGAUUCCUGCUGUGUUUUUCUUGAGGAACAUUCCAUGUGAUUUAGACUUUAAGGGCACACAGUGUCCAAACCCUUCCUCCUAUAUUCCUAGAUUACUAACGACCAAUUCAGACCACAUGACAUUCCUGCAAAGGGUCAAGAACAUGCUCUACCCUCUGGCCCUGUCCUACCUUUGCCAUGCUGUUUCUGCUCCUUAUGCAAGCCUUGCCUCUGAGCUUUUUCAGAGAGAGGUGUCAGUGGUGGAUCUUGUCAGCCAUGCAUCUGUGUGGCUGUUCCGAGGGGACUUUGUGAUGGAUUACCCCAGGCCGAUCAUGCCCAACAUGGUCUUCAUUGGGGGCAUCAACUGUGCCAACGGGAAGCCACUAUCUCAGGAAUUUGAAGCCUACAUUAAUGCUUCUGGAGAACAUGGAAUUGUGGUUUUCUCUUUGGGAUCAAUGGUCUCAGAAAUUCCAGAGAAGAAAGCUAUGGCAAUUGCUGAUGCUUUGGGCAAAAUCCCUCAGACAGUCCUGUGGCGGUACACUGGAACCCGACCAUCGAAUCUUGCGAACAACACGAUACUUGUUAAGUGGCUACCCCAAAACGAUCUGCUUGGUCACCCGAUGACCCGUGCCUUUAUCACCCAUGCUGGUUCCCAUGGUGUUUAUGAAAGCAUAUGCAAUGGCGUUCCCAUGGUGAUGAUGCCCUUGUUUGGUGAUCAGAUGGACAAUGCAAAGCGCAUGGAGACUAAGGGAGCUGGAGUGACCCUGAAUGUUCUGGAAAUGACUUCUGAAGAUUUAGAAAAUGCUCUAAAAGCAGUCAUCAAUGACAAAAGUUACAAGGAGAACAUCAUGCGCCUCUCCAGCCUUCACAAGGACCGCCCGGUGGAGCCGCUGGACCUGGCCGUGUUCUGGGUGGAGUUUGUGAUGAGGCACAAGGGCGCGCCACACCUGCGCCCCGCAGCCCACGACCUCACCUGGUACCAGUACCAUUCCUUGGACGUGAUUGGUUUCCUCUUGGCCGUCGUGCUGACAGUGGCCUUCAUCACCUUUAAAUGUUGUGCUUAUGGCUACCGGAAAUGCUUGGGGAAAAAAGGGCGAGUUAAGAAAGCCCACAAAUCCAAGACCCAUUGAGAAGUGGGUGGGAAAUAAGGUAAAAUUUUGAACCAUUCCCUAGUCAUUUCCAAACUUGAAAACAGAAUCAGUGUUAAAUUCAUUUUAUUCUUAUUAAGGAAAUACUUUGCAUAAAUUAAUCAGCCCCAGAGUGCUUUAAAAAAUUCUCUUAAAUAAAAAUAAUAGACUCGCUAGUCAGUAAAGAUAUUUGAAUAUGUAUCGUGCCCCCUCUGGUGUCUUUGAUCAGGAUGACAUGUGCCAUUUUUCAGAGGACGUGCAGACAGGCUGGCAUUCUAGAUUACUUUUCUUACUCUGAAACAUGGCCUGUUUGGGAGUGCGGGAUUCAAAGGUGGUCCCACGGCUGCCCCUACUGCAAAUGGCAGUUUUAAUCUUAUCUUUUGGCUUCUGCAGAUGGUUGCAAUUGAUCCUUAACCAAUAAUGGUCAGUCCUCAUCUCUGUCGUGCUUCAUAGGUGCCACCUUGUGUGUUUAAAGAAGGGAAGCUUUGUACCUUUAGAGUGUAGGUGAAAUGAAUGAAUGGCUUGGAGUGCACUGAGAACAGCAUAUGAUUUCUUGCUUUGGGGAAAAAGAAUGAUGCUAUGAAAUUGGUGGGUGGUGUAUUUGAGAAGAUAAUCAUUGCUUAUGUCAAAUGGAGCUGAAUUUGAUAAAAACCCAAAAUACAGCUAUGAAGUGCUGGGCAAGUUUACUUUUUUUCUGAUGUUUCCUACAACUAAAAAUAAAUUAAUAAAUUUAUAUAAAUUCUA